CGCAAGAUAGCAGAGGUGGCGCGCAGCCCGGCGAGCCGAUGACGGACCCCUUCUUCCUGCCUUCAAUGCCUCAGCGGAAGAUCCCCAAGGGCUGGAGCGAGGAGCGCUGCCGCUGGACAUCCUCCCGGGGAGGCUGCUCCGACCUGCUGCGCGGCGCGUCUGAGACUGGGGACUGAGCCACCCCGCCGCCGCCGGCGCCGCCGCCGCCGCCCGCUCCGUCGCUGCCGUCGGUCUGGACUGGCCCCCACCUCGCUGCGCCCUCUCCCCGGCCCCGGCCCCGGCUCGGGGCGUCCCGGGGCUCGCCCUGCGACCGCCGCCUCCCGCGCGCCGCGUCCUCCCGACCCCGCGGCGGCGACGAUGCCCGGGAGGAGGGUCCUGACGGCGGCGGCGCGGAUGGUGGCGGCCGGCGCCCGGGUGUGAUGCGAGCGUCACGGUGGGGAUGCUGCUGGCUGCGCGGCGCUGAGGGCCAGCGAGAGCGAGAGCCCGCCCGGGGCGGAGGACGGACUCAUCCGGAUCUGGCUGCAGCGUGGGCUCGGAGCUCCCCCUUCCUCUCGGUCUCCCUCUCGGCCCCCCUUUAUUUCCUUCUUGCUUUGCGUCUUUAACACCUCUCGACCCUGUCCUCCCCCCGCCACUGGAAGUCUUCCCGUCUCUAAAUGGAAUUAGUGGAGCCCGGAGCCUCUGGUGUAACGCACAGACAUGAUCCAUGGGCGCAGCGUGCUUCACAUUGUAGCAAGUUUAAUCAUCCUCCAUUUGUCUGGGGCAACCAAGAAAGGAACAGAAAAGCAAACCACCUCAGAAACACAGAAGUCAGUGCAGUGUGGAACUUGGACAAAACAUGCAGAGGGAGGUAUCUUUACCUCUCCCAACUAUCCCAGCAAGUAUCCCCCUGACCGGGAAUGCAUCUACAUCAUAGAAGCCGCUCCAAGACAGUGCAUUGAACUUUACUUUGAUGAAAAGUACUCUAUUGAACCGUCUUGGGAGUGCAAAUUUGAUCAUAUUGAAGUUCGAGAUGGACCUUUUGGCUUUUCUCCAAUAAUUGGACGUUUCUGUGGACAACAAAAUCCACCUGUCAUAAAAUCCAGUGGAAGAUUUCUAUGGAUUAAAUUUUUUGCUGAUGGAGAGCUGGAAUCUAUGGGAUUUUCAGCUCGAUACAAUUUCACACCUGACCAUUACUCUGGGAAAGCCUCGGAUUAUUUUUCUCACCUCUUAAUGAAAUCACCUUCCAUGCUCUUGUUCUUGAAUGACAGAAAAACGAGCGAGGAACUACAGAUUGAGCAGGUAUCUCAUAAACAGCUGUGUCUUAAGCAGAAUUGUAGGAGCAAGUGCACCAUUUCAGAGUGCUUUUGUAAUGCAGUGCCUUUUCAAAAUUACAGAUUUUCUAAAUGCCAGUGGAAAGAAGUGGUAUAACACUGUUAAAAAUUCUAAGACUUCCAUUUUAGCACUAUUUCCAGUUGUAUUUGAUAUGGGCUGUAAGUGGUCUCCAUUCUUACAGUCCUUAAGAGAUGAUACGUUUGCAUGCCAAAUGCACCCUGGCAGUUAGGUCUGGAGGUCCAGGAAUAAUCAUUCUUCACAUUCCCCAAGAUGGAGACUAUGCUUUCUAGAGAUAAUUCUUUCAGAGGCAGAAUGUGGUCCCAAACUAGCCAGCUGACAUGAUUACUUCCAUUUUCGAGUAGAGUCCCCAUUAAAAUUACUGGUUUCAGAUGCCCGUUCAAACCUAAAUUACUGUAAUAAUUGGGAAAAUAAGUACAAAGGAGACAAAUACAAGAAAUAGAGAUGGGAAGAUUUGAAUAUUUUGGUAAUCAUGUACUUAGUCUGUAUUUAAAAUGGACCAAGAUUACUUGAUAUUGUAGAAUGCAAAUAAAUCCUUUAAGCUCUCAGAUAGUUGUACACUUCCAGGAGAUGACCUCUUAAAUUGCAAACAGUGACAUUAGACACAAUGUUUUAUUUUUUUAGAAAAAGUUUCAUACAUAUUUAGAUUAGCUUGGUUUUACCAUUAUUUACACUGAAGGUAUUAUUUUCGAGCUAAAUAGACGUAAAAGGGACUUGCGCACCUAGCAUAUGAUGCUAUAUAUUAAAGGAAAAGUGGCUAUCUUGGCAUGUAGCAAGUAUCUAUCAUCACUUUGAUAUUUGCAGUAUGCAGAAAAAACUAUGUUAGGAAAUUUUCUGAGGGUAUUUUCCUACUGAUCUCAGGCAUUUGAAGACAUACAGUUAACUUCUCUUUCAUCUCAACAUUAAAUGCUAUCUAAUAAAAAUAAGUGCAGUGUGCAGAAUAGCCAAUGAGGCUACAACAACAGUAUUUGAUUUGUAAAUAAAUUUUAUAGAGCAGUAAUCAUAUUUGAGAUAUUCUUUGAAUUAAGAUAAUUUUUAUUCAUGUAUCGAAGAGGUUCGAAAUCUGAAUUGUACAUGCAUGGGAUAAUUUAUUUUUACAUAACAUUUUAUACUUUAGCAAAUCCAUAUCCACUCUAUUAACUAGUUGAUACGUGCAAAUACUACUGCUUUGUACCAAGCCUGGUUGAUAUUUUUUACCCCAGUCUCUUAGAAGCGAGGCAAUUGAUGCCUUAGAAGGUAGAAUUCUGUCAAUAAGUGUUAGUUACAUACAGGUUCAGCAUAUUAAAUUUUCCUCGUCGGUGGCUUUUUAAGAAAUUAAGUAUUUGACAUACUUUUGAUUAUUUUCAUUUGGGUUUUGAGUCUGUUUUGUUUAACAUAAUAUCAUUACAAAAGCUUUUUAUCAUUUAUUUAUUGCUUGUCUGGCAUAUAUUUUUUUGCCUUUUUAAUUUCUACCUAUCUGCGUCAGUAUAUGCCUUAUGUGUGGCUUUUAUAAAAAGUGGGUGGCUGAGUUUUCUAGAUGUGACGAGCAGAGUGAUGGCUAGAACUUACAGAUUCUGCCCUUGGUAAAGGAAUGAGAAUCAUAACUUAAAAGGACACAUUUACUUUUACAGAAUAUGAUAACUUUACCUCUUUUCCAGACUGACAGAAAUUCAUGCAGUGCAAACAGCUUCUCCAGGAUUGACCAAGAGGUGCCUCAUGCAUGCACCCGUGCCAGGCUCCUGGCAAGGCACCACUUGGCAUUCUGCAUUUGCUCUCUUGGUCCCAUGAUGGAUCCUCCACUUGCCAUGUGUCCCACUGCUGCCUGGCAUGAAAACUCCAGUGUCCUUGCCAAGGGCACCAACAGAGAACACUGCUAAAGUUUCCAGCAAGAGGCUGCUCCAGCUCUAUUUAGAAGGGUCUAAUAUUCAUCAAAUUCACUGGGAGCACAAAAGGUCUUGUCUUGAAGCUCCGUUAGCAUGGCUUGUACAGCUUUAUUGUGUCCUUAUCUUAUUUAUGUGGCUGUAACACACAAGGCUUUGCCAUGAUGCUUAAACGUACAUCUUUAAAUAAUUUUGAGAAAGCAUAACUUUUCUUGUAAAAUAUUUUGCUUCUUGAUUUUCAUUGACACCAUUUAUUUAGUUUACAGUGGCAUAAUUGGGAUGGAAGAGGACAACGUGAGAUUAAUGCCAUCUCCUCACCACACACACACUCCACACACACACACACACACACACACACACACACACAAAUCUGCAGUGCCACCACUGCUUCCAACCUGUGUGUAGCAGAGACAGCAUUUUCCUCCUCUGCAACCUAUGUCACGCUUGUAAGCCUGGGUCCCAAAGACUGCACUUCGUUAUUCCUAGACACUCAUGUAGUUCUUAGGAGAAGUUAUGUCUUCUCACUUUUCUGGGCAUAAAAGCUCAGCCCCAGUCUAAUAUCACCUGCCUUGGCAUCAGCUCCAGAACCUUCUGUAGCCUGCUGUUUCUCCCUCCUCCUGAUUAAUUGCCAGUGGUUUCUGUGCUUAUCAAUAAGCUGGAAUUGAUAGUGGGAAAACAGUGAAUGUGGCAUAAUUGAGAAAAGAGGAUAAUAAUGGAGGCGUUUUAUUCACUAAUAGCACUGGCACCACAUUUCUGCCAACAAGAAAUGCCCUAUUAAACCAGUUCUAGUGAAAAAGAUGGCUCAGGAGAUGGGCUCAUGUAUUCUUUGUGUGACUUAGGAUGAGCAAAUAACAGCAUUCUGAGAGAAUUAAGGGGCAGGGAUAUUGCUAAUAACCAAUCAAGAGCGUCCCUGGUUGCCCUUGGACAGAAACAACAACAGCAACAGCAACAUACAACAACAACAAGAACAACAAAACUUAUUCUAUGACAGCUAAUUCAAAUGUGCAAACUCCAGCAUUUGGACAGUAUGGGUGUGUGUGUGUGUGUGUGUGUGUGUGUGUGUGUGUGUGUUCUUGUCUUCAUUGUUCUGUUUCUGCCCAUUUUUGAUCGUCUGAUGAUUUCUUCUUCACUCUAUCCCCCACAUCUUUCUAUGAUUAUGUUUAGUAAAUGCAUAUUUUCUCUGUAGAACAGUAGUAUUGCCUUGUUACUAUCUAUCAGAAGUAAACAUUGUAAAAGCCUACUUAAUGUGAACACAAACAAAAUCCAACUUCUGUGUACUCGUGUUAUAAGAGUUACGUUUUCUCAAUUUGUUUAAAAAUGUGAAUACACGCACCAUGAGGAAACUUCAAAUUACAGCUAAAUAAAUAAAAUAAGGGAACAAAAAAGCUUUACAAGCCCAGCACAUAUCAAUAAUAUUUUAAAGGGCUUGAAAAUUUUCUUCCUGUAAAUCUUGUAAGUUUUGGUUUCUUAAAUUUAUAUAUGAAUAAAAUUUAUGUUAAACUAGAAAAGAAAGUCAGGUUAUAUAUACUCUGUGCCCACAUGAAAACCAUUAGGUAGACAGACUCAAAAAGAGAAGCUAUAAUUGUCAACCCCAUACUUAGAGAAAAGAGUAUACCUUUAAAAGAAGUUUAAAACAUGGUGAUAUGAAUUUUAUACUAGAGCAAUGCUGCUUCUAGACGAGUGAAUUAACUCAGAGUAUUAAAACAAUAUGAUUAUGCAAGCUAUUCUUUACUCUGCUGUUAAGAUUUUUCUGCCAUUGAUAUUUAAAAUGGCACUUAAAGUUUGUUCAAAUGAUUUCAAAAACUACAAACACUCUGGUUUUCAACCUUGAGUAAAAAACAAGGGGUCCAACACCUGUUGCAGACAAGUAUGGAAGGAUGGAAAUAAGAAUGUCCCCAUUGAAGGGUGUGGUUAGUUUCAAAUUAGACAUUGUUUCAGUAAAGAUGUGUACACAAACAUGAUGGGACUUUCAAAAGUGAGUAGGAGAUUGGAUGUGAAGAUUGAUUAUGGAUCGCAGGUCUAAGAAAUGGAAGUCAGUCAUCUGGGAAUUGAAUGAGAACAAGGAAGAGUGAGUGGACAGUGGGAAGCAAGGUGAAGGAGGAGUUUGCGUUGUGUUAUUAGCUAAGAAGGGACUUGAGCAGAUUUAUUGUCUGAAAGGUUGUAGAUAAUAGAAGGUAGUUUAAAAAUUUUAGGAAGAUAAUUGAUGUGCUCACUACUAUGAAUAGGGGUGAUGAGAAAAUCCAGAAGAUAGGUAGAGAAUUCGAUUUAGAGAGAUUAAUUUUUCAGAAUUGGAGGAAGAUAAUUGAUAUGCCAACUACUAUGUAUAGGAGUGAUUAGAAAAUCCAUACGGUAGGUGGAGAAUUAGAUUUAGAGAGAGAAAGUGUUGGUAGAUAGGCAGUAAUGACAGUGGAUCUGGAUGAGUUUAUAGGUUGAGAGUGGGAAGUUGAAUAACUUCCUAGCUCAUGGAGUCUUUGUUGAUGUUAAUGAGAAAACUAAACAUUGUCCCUGAUUGUUUUCUCCUUCACUUCCCACACCCAAUCCAUCAGUAAACCUAAAAUAAAGUGAUUGGUCAUUGAAUGUUAACUGUAGGGUUUGUAAAUUUGAUCAACUUGCUUGAACCCAAAUAUGAUCAUAUGCUUGGAAGAACUAAUCACAGAAUUACUGGGCUUCAGGGUGAAAAGGACGUCGUAGGUAAUGUCGUCUACCAACCCACCCCCCACGAAGCCUACACAAAUACUUGUUUCCUGGGGCAGCAUUUAGUACACCUCAUCAUUAGCUUUCAACACACAGCUCUAAUUUAUUCCUCUGUAGGACAAAUGAAAAAGAUUUACUUACGUGGAUCUUGAUCUCUGAAAUUCAUUUUUGAAACAUUUUGAACAUAUUUGUGUUUUUAACCAUAGCUCCAACAUCAUACUCAAACAUAUUUUUCCCCUGCCAAAAAAAAAUUGUAUUUUAUCUGUUUUAUAUAUAAAAUUGCUUUAGGUUACGUCACUCCCAAAUCAAGAGAGAAGGAAGAACAGCCACAUGGAGAGUCCAGACAGGCCCAGUAGACCAGAUGACAUUCUUAGCAUUUACAAGUCUGUAAUGAAUUCAAAUAGAAUGUGACAAUAUGGAAAUCUGGAGGUCGACUGCCUAAUUCUGAUUUCAAGUCCUACCAUUUACAACUGUAUUCUUAGGCUAGUUACUUAAUCUCUCUGUGCUGCCUGUUUUCCUCAGCUAUAAAACAAGCAUAGCACUGUUAUCUACAUCAUACAGUGUUAAGGAAUAAAGGACUUACUAUAUUUAAAGUAAUUAAAAUAAUAUCUGGUACAUAUUAAUUAUUGCAAUGGUAUUAGCUAUUUUCGUGGAUCUAACUAAAUGAAAAUAAGAAUUAAAAUGAGAAACCAGAAAAAACCCUUUUAGUCACGUAGAUAUAUUUCAAACUUGUAUUCUUUUCAUUUGUGUAGAAUAUUUGAGAACUCUGUCUCAUAAAAAUUUGAUUCAUUUGUAUUUUAGUUUGUAUUAUAGGAAAAUUCUUGAAGAUUAUAGUGGAGUGCUUAAAAAUACAAAUUGAUUCUAAAGUCUGCAUUCUCUUUUGUAACAUAAAUACUAAUUUCUAUCAAAAUACUGGAUUCAUUUUUCUAUGGCCAAUUAAUAAAUGGUUUGCAGUUAAA